ACUCUGGGCGGCGGAUCCGAGCGGGGGAUACCCCAGGAGAUGGGGGUCGAGGAGAGACCCCGGGGAGUAGAGAGAGAGAAACUCACUCCCCGAGUCCCCGACCCUCCCCAAGCAAGGUUAUAAUAUAACUUAUCCUCUCAUGCUUUUUUCCUGCCCCUUCUCCCCAAAUCAUCAACAAUAGAAGAAGAAGAAAACAUGUCAGGACACAAAUGCAGUUAUCCCUGGGACUUACAGGAUCGAUAUGCUCAAGAUAAGUCAGUUGUAAAUAAGAUGCAACAGAAAUAUUGGGAGACGAAGCAGGCCUUUAUUAAAGCCACAGGGAAGAAGGAAGAUGAACAUGUUGUUGCCUCUGACGCGGACCUGGAUGCCAAGCUAGAGCUGUUUCAUUCAAUUCAGAGAACCUGUCUGGACUUAUCGAAAGCAAUUGUACUCUAUCAAAAGAGGAUAUGUUCAUUUUAGGAGGCCAAGGCAGGAGGAUCACUUGGAGCCAGGAGUUUGAGACCAGCCUGGGCAACAAAGUGAGACCCCCAUCUCUACAAAAAAUAAAAACACUUAAAAAUUAUCCGGGUACCGUGCAUGUGCAGUCCCAGCUACUCAGGAGGCUGAGGCAGGAGGAUCACAGUGACCUAUAAUGAGCCGUUGUGCUCCAGCCUGGGCGACAGAAGUCUUGUCUCAAGAAGAAAACGAACUGGGAAAAUUUCUUCGAUCCCAAGGUUUCCAAGAUAAAACCAGAGCAGGAAAGAUGAUGCAAGCGACAGGAAAGGCCCUCUGCUUUUCUUCCCAGCAAAGGUUGGCCUUACGAAAUCCUUUGUGUCGAUUUCACCAAGAAGUGGAGACUUUUCGGCAUCGGGCCAUCUCAGAUACUUGGCUGACGGUGAACCGCAUGGAACAGUGCAGGACGGAAUAUAGAGGAGCACUAUUAUGGAUGAAGGACGUGUCUCAGGAGCUUGAUCCAGACCUCUACAAGCAAAUGGAGAAGUUCAGGAAGGUACAAACACAAGUGCGCCUUGCAAAAAAAAACUUUGACAAAUUGAAGAUGGAUGUUUGUCAAAAAGUGGAUCUUCUUGGAGCGAGCAGAUGCAAUCUCUUGUCUCACAUGCUAGCAACAUACCAGACCACUCUGCUUCAUUUUUGGGAGAAAACUUCUCACACUAUGGCAGCCAUCCAUGAGAGUUUCAAAGGUUAUCAACCAUAUGAAUUUACUACUUUAAAGAGCUUACAAGACCCUAUGAAAAAAUUAGUUGAGAAAGAAGAGAAGAAGAAAAUCAACCAGCAGGAAAGUACAGAUGCAGCCGUGCAGGAGCCGAGCCAAUUAAUUUCAUUAGAGGAAGAAAACCAGCGCAAGGAAUCCUCUAGUUUUAAGACUGAAGAUGGAAAAAGUAUUUUAUCUGCCUUAGACAAAGGCUCUACACAUACUGCAUGCUCAGGACCCAUAGAUGAACUAUUAGACAUGAAAUCUGAGGAAGGUGCUUGCCUGGGACCAGUGGCAGGGACCCCGGAACCUGAAGGUGCUGACAAAGAUGACCUGCUGCUGUUGAGUGAGAUCUUCAAUGCUUCCUCCUUGGAAGAGGGCGAGUUCAGCAAAGAGUGGGCCGCUGUGUUUGGAGACGGCCAAGUGAAGGAGCCAGUGCCCACUAUGGCCCUGGGAGAGCCAGACCCCAAGGCCCAGACAGGCUCAGGUUUCCUUCCUUCGCAGCUUUUAGACCAAAAUAUGAAAGACUUACAGGCCUCGCUACAAGAACCUGCUAAGGCUGCCUCAGACCUGACUGCCUGGUUCAGCCUCUUCGCUGACCUCGACCCACUCUCAAAUCCUGAUGCUGUUGGGAAAACCGAUAAAGAACACGAAUUGCUCAAUGCAUGAAUCUGUACCCUUCGGGAGGGCACUCACAUGCCGCCCCCAGCAGCUCCCCUGGGGGCUAGCAGAAGUAUAAAGUGAUCAGUAUGCUGUUUUAAUAAUUAUGUGCCAUUUUAAUAAAAUGAAAGGGUCAACGGCCCUGUUUAUAUUGGUAUAAUUAUUUACUCUUAUUUGGUAUAAAGGGUUUUCGUGUAUCUCUAUGUGGAUCUAAAUAAUACAGGAUUGUCUAGAAGCGGUUUCCAGGCCACCGCUCUCCUGCCUACAUCCCAUCAUGGCUGCUGCGGUGUCACUGGGCUACCGUGAGAUCCAAGUUGAAAUCAGAAGCCUACUUUGAUGGUAGGUUUGAAUGACGUGUCCUACAGCCUCAGAGGCAGCAGGAGGCUAGCAAAGCUUAAAUGCCUCCUUCUCUGCCCCCAGCCUCUGUCCCCCUUGGAGGAGGGCUGUAGGAAGAUUCCCUCUUCCUGCCAAGCCACCUUCCAGUGAGCUCUGGAUGAAGCUCUGGCCAACCAAAGACACUGUCCCCACAGCAGGUGCCUGGUGGGCCACGUGUUCUCACACUGGUGGAGGAGCUGGGCUUCUGUCCAAGGCACAAACCUUACUAUGGAAAGCAGCCAUAUUUGCAGAUACCACUGUCUCCUUUUGUCCUCUUCGUGGCUGGAAUUCAAAAGCAUGUAUUUCUGAAGCCUCUUGUGACAUUGUUUUUUUUUUUUUUUUAAUUAAACAGAAAAGAUAUUUGACAUGCAAA